AUUUUUUUUAGGUAAAUGAGAAUAGCAGAAAGUAUCAGCAAAAUGAAGACUCAACUGUUUUGGGGAUUUAUACUCCCUUUCAGUCUCCUUCUAUUAAGAAUUAAAUGAGACCCAAAGCCCCCACCCCCGUGUUUUUUUUUAAAGUCUCACCAAAGUAAGCAGAAUAGACCCUUUCUUAAUAUAGUGAUUUGGUCUCUUUUCACAAAACUGCUAAUAAACUACCUACAUGAUUUUGAAGGAUGGAGAUUCUACACUUCUAUGUGUAGCAUGCUGCAACAGUUAAUAAACCUUAAAUUCUAGACACUGUUUCUCAUAUAUAAUCUAAAUGUCUCUUGCAGGAUUUUAUUUUCUUCUUCAUGGAACUUUUGUGGGUGUUUUUGGUGGGGGGGUACGAAAGCUCUUGAAGUUAUUCCUUCAUAUUCUUGAAAAUGAUUCUCAGUUAAUUCCAAGUCUUUUUAAUCUUUCCUUAUAGAUGCCAUCUGACUACUCCCUAUUGGGAUUGGUGUUUGCAGUGGUGUUCUUUCCUAUACUCACUUCUAGCUUAUCAUUUUCUUAAAGCGUAGUGCCCCAUAAUAUAAAUAUUGUCCAAACUGUCCAAAUUCAGUACUUCAAAAUAUAAAACAAAACAUGUCCAACCCCACAGAAAUAUAUCAUAAAAUAGACUGGGCACAGUGGCUCAUGCCUGUAAUCCCAGCACUUUGGGAGGCUGAUGCGGGCGGAUCACUUUUGGCCAGGAGUUCAAGACAAGCCUGGCCAACAUGGUGAAACCCCAUCUCUACUAAAAAUACAAAAAUUAGCUGGGCAUGGUGGCACAUGCCUGUAGUCCCAGCUACUUGGGAGGAUGAGGCACAAGAAUCACUUGAACCCUGGAGGUGGGGGUUGCAGUAAGCCGAGAUCGCACCACUGCACUCCAGCCUGGGUGACAGAGCAAGACUCUUGUCUCACAGAAAGAGAAACAUACAAAAUAAAAAUGUUUACUUUCAGGUUAUCUUUCUUUGAAGUACAAUUGCAAGAUCUUACCAAACACCUGCUUCCUCUCUUUUUCUUUUGUUAAAUUGACUCCCCAGGCUCCUCUUUUCUCCUUAUUCCUUUAUCUGUGCAGUAUAAAUUAUGAUAUACUAAUUACUUACCUGUUUAAUUUUUUCAUUAAUGAACAACUCCUACCCCAAUACACAAUGAAAGGGACUCAAGCCUCUAUUCCAAUCUUGCAACUUCUAAUAGUGAAUAUCAAAUAAAUCCAGGAUGGGAGUGGUGACUUAUACCUGCAAUCCCAGUGCAUUGGAAGGCUGAGGUAGGAAGACUGUUUGAGGCCUGGAACUUGAGACCAGUCUGGGCAACAGAGCAAGAUCCCAUCUCUACUAAAAAUAAAAAAAUUAGUUGAGUGUGGAGGUGCACGCCUGAAGUCCCAACAAGAGGCUGAGGUGGGAGGAUCGGUUCCCACAACUUGUAAACUUGACCCCAGGAGUUCAAGUUUACAGUGCGCUAUGAUCAUGUCACUGUACUCCAACCUGGAUGAAACAGCGAGACAGACCUUGUCUCUAAAACAUAAACAAAACAAACAAGCAAAACCCCAUAAUAACAUGGUGGGCCCAAAUAACUUCUAUGUAAAUAAAAAACAGUAAUUUAUACUACAGCUGAUAUUUAAUGUGUUUUAUGCAGGAAAUACUUAUUAAAAUAAUCAGCAGAGAAUGUGAUUGGCUGUAAGUAAAAACAAAAGAUUUCUGUUGAAAGUUAUUUCUUUCAAUUGCUUUUAAGUAUGAAUAAAAACCUCAAAAGGUGACACUUAAGAUGGCUUAACACAGGCUAUCUGCUGGUGAAUAUAAUUUGAAAACAACUCACAUGAUAAAAACUUACAAUGUAUAAAUCACAAAUGAGGAAACUGCUCAUGAAACCUCCACCAAUUCAAACCUCACUUCUGAAAAUACAGAUAUCCUUCUAUAACAAUUCUUUACCAUAUGGUAAGUGGCGUAACAACAAAAGCAAAAAGCCAAGUGUCAAACUGCAUCUUAUUGAUAAGACCUUUAUUUAGCUGACUGCUCCACAUAUGCUACACAUCAAAAGGAAAGAAUGUAAAUCAGGUUAGGACAAGUACCCUCCAUUUGUUAUUACUGAGCUAUCAAACAACAUCUGGUUAACAGGAAUUAUUAUAUACAGUAGUAAGAAGAGUUUCCAAGUUUGGGCAAGAUAACUGAAUCAAGAGAGAGAUUUUUAAUUAAAAGUUGGCAUUUUUAUUAAAACCUUCUAUCCAAGGAUUUAGAGCUGUACAAACUCUUGACUAAACCUCAGAAGUAAGGUACCCAUAAUUUUGGAAGUCACCAGUUUGUAUUCUGUCAACAGAAAAAUAUAUAUAAAGAGUUAAAGUUGUGGUUUAUUGAGCAAGUAGAGCUAAACUGAUGAAUCUCUAUGUUUUUUAUCUCGUGGAGUACAAUAAAAGUCAGUAACGAACUUGGAUUUUUUUCUUUUUUUGAGACAGAGUCUUGCUCUGUCGCCCAGGCUAGAGUGCAGUGGCACGAUCUCGGCUCACUGCAACUUCUGCCUCCUGGGUUCAGGCGAUUCUCCUGCCUCAGCCUCCCGAGUAGCUGGCAUUACAGGUGCCCACCACCACGCCUAGCUAAUUUAUGUAUUUUUAUUAGAGAUGGGGUUUCAGCGUGUUGGCCAGGCUGGUCUCAAACUCCUGACCUUGUGACCCACUGUGGCCAGCCAUGAACUUGGAUUUUUAAGUGGCCUUCCCCAUUCUGGUCCCUAUUGUCUUGCUCACUGCACUCAUACUGAACCACUGGAAACUCCAUAUUGUAGCUCCACAAUCUGAAUUAUCCUUUCCUGAAUAAUCCUAGGUGAUACGUGUGAAGAUCACAUCAGGCACCUUCCUAAAAUGAUAUAGCACAGAUAGCUGCAAACCUGACUUUCAAAACUGGACAGAAGUAAUAACUCUCUCAUAGAAGGAUUUUCCUGAGCGUUCAUAAUUUAUUUCCAAAUUUGCAAAAUCAAACGAGUAGGCAGUUAUAAAAUGACACGGAACAACACUCCUCAUACUCCACAUAAUCUUUCUUACAGAAUAAAGAGCUGUGAGAAUGUCUAUGUGAAUAAAAUGUCACCAGAAAGCAUGCUUCUCUAUGGUUUGGGGUUGGAGGAAGGGACAGGAAGUGAAAGGCCACACACUUUUCUGUACCUAUCAGAUUUGAGAAAUUACUGGGUUCAUGCAGAGUUCUGCUGCAGUAGGGAGACCUGUUCUGCUGAUUACCAUGCAUAAAGGUGAUGAAGAUGUAAAGACUGCUAAAAGAUAACAUUGGGCUGAAAAGAAAAUUUUUUUAAACACUCAUUCUCUCACCCUUCAGAAGUUAGGGCUGGGAAGGAGAAGGUAGGAAGAUUAUUUCUGUCAAACAGCCAUACCUUCAAUGUGUACAUGCACAGGCACUAUGUUUAUCACUUUAACCAAUUAAAACAAAUGGGUAUUAUAAUACCUGACACUUUGAAGGCUUACAAUCAAACAAACGCAAAAGCCGUCUGGGAUAGAUGAGGCACUAAUUAAUAAUGGGUUGGGUAAGUAAAGAAUCUAAAAGAAGAGGUUUAACAGCAUAGUCUUAUUUUAGGAGGCUAUACGGUUAUAUUUGAGGAAAUCACACUUAAUUUUCCCAAAUGUGUUUUAGGUGCAACCUAUCCAGUCACUUUCCUUUUGAGAGCUGAAGUACCUGAAGCUUUGGAGAUGGUAAAGGAAUUAUUGAGGGUCAUACUGGCUAAGAAGAGUGCUAAAAGUGGAGACCUUUAUCACAAAGAUUUUAGCAUCGAAACUAGGAGAAAUAAGAAUGGCUGUAGAGGAACUUCAGUCUAUAAUAAAGAGAUGUCAAAUCCUAGAAGAGCAAGACUUUAAAGAAGAGGAUUUUGGCCUAUUUCAGUUAGCUGGGCAAAGAUGCAUAGAAGAAGGGCACACAGACCAGCUAUUAGAAAUUAUUCAAAAUGAAAAGAAUAAGGUCAUCAUCAAGAAUAUGGGCUGGAAUCUCGUUGGUCCUGUUGUUCGAUGCCUUUUGUGUAAAGAUAAAGAGGAUAGUAAAAGAAAAGUUUAUUUUUUGAUCUUUGAUUUAUUGGUAAAGUUAUGCAAUCCAAAGGAAUUAUUGUUGGGUUUGCUUGAACUGAUUGAAGAGCCCUCUGGAAAACAGAUAUCCCAAAGUAUUCUUCUUUUGCUUCAGCCAUUACAAACAGUGAUUCAGAAACUUCAUAACAAGGCAUAUUCAAUUGGAUUAGCAUUGUCUACCCUUUGGAAUCAGCUAUCUCUUCUUCCUGUUCCAUACUCAAAAGAACAAAUACAAAUGGAUGACUAUGGCCUUUGUCAGUGUUGCAAGGCCUUAAUAGAGUUCACUAAGCCUUUUGUGGAAGAAGUCAUUGAUAACAAAGAAAACUCACUGGAAAAUGAAAAGUUAAAGGAUGAAUUACUGAAAUUUUGUUUCAAAAGCUUGAAAUGCCCUUUGCUGACAGCACAAUUCUUUGAACAGUCUGAAGAAGGUGGAAAUGAUCCUUUCAGGUAUUUUGCAUCAGAAAUAAUAGGUUUUUUAUCAGCAAUUGGACACCCUUUCCCCAAAAUGAUUUUUAAUCAUGGAAGGAAAAAGAGAACUUGGAAUUACCUUGAAUUUGAAGAAGAAGAAAAUAAACAGUUAGCAGACUCAAUGGCUUCUCUGGCAUAUCUAGUAUUUGUACAGGGCAUCCAUAUUGAUCAGCUUCCAAUGGUCUUAAGCCCAUUGUACCUUUUGCAGUUUAAUAUGGGGCACAUUGAAGUCUUUUUGCAAAGAACAGAAGAGUCUGUUAUCUCCAAAGGAUUGGAGCUGCUGGAGAAUAGUUUAUUGAGAAUAGAAGACAAUAGUCUACUUUACCAGUACUUAGAAAUCAAGAGUUUUCUUACUGUACCUCAGGGCUUAGUGAAAGUAAUGACACUUUGCCCCAUUGAGACACUGAGGAAAAAGAGUUUAGCUAUGCUUCAGCUGUAUAUUAACAAGUUGGAUUCACAAGGCAAAUAUACAUUAUUUAGGUGCUUAUUGAAUACAAGUAAUCACUCAGGUGUGGAGGCUUUUAUUAUUCAAAAUAUCAAAAAUCAAAUUGACAUGUCAUUAAAGAGAACACGUAACAACAAAUGGUUUACAGGACCACAGUUGAUUUCCCUUCUUGAUUUGGUACUUUUUCUCCCAGAGGGUGCAGAAACAGAUUUACUGCAAAACUCAGAUAGGAUUAUGGCUUCAUUAAAUUUAUUGAGGUAUUUGGUUAUCAAAGAUAAUGAAAAUGACAAUCAAACUGGAUUAUGGACAGAACUUGGAAAUAUUGAGAAUAAUUUCUUAAAGCCACUUCAUAUAGGACUUAAUAUGUCAAAAGCACAUUAUGAAGCAGAAAUUAAAAAUAGCCAAGAGGCCCAGAAAUCUAAAGAUCUUUGUUCUAUAACUGUAAGUGGAGAAGAGAUCCCUAAUAUGCCUCCUGAAAUGCAGCUUAAGGUCCUGCAUUCAGCUCUUUUCACAUUUGAUUUGAUUGAAAGUGUUCUAGCUCGAGUGGAAGAACUCAUUGAAAUAAAAACAAAGUCUACCUCUGAAGAAAAUAUUGGGAUAAAGUGAAAGUUCCAUUUCCUAAAUAAAAACUAAUAAAAUAUAGUACUUUCCAUUAUGAUUCAUUUAAUACCUUUAUAAAAAAUUUUUCUGUAAAAAUUUACUGCUUGAAAAAUAAAUGUAGCUUUUCUCAUUUA